AAUCCAAACCUUCAUGGUGCUGUGUGGCUGGGUGGAGGGAACGACUCGGCAGCCUCUUCUGGCCCUGAGGAAGACGUCGAUAUUUUGGCACGAGGGGAGCCACUGAAGGACUACCCUACCCUUGCGAGGGACCGCAGGAGGUGACGCCCCUGGGCCUCGGUGGGCGCUUCUGGCGGUUUUCGAUGUGGCAACCCCCAUCAGCCAGGAUAAUGAUGAGGCAGGUACAAUCUAUCUAGUACGCAGCCCCCAGACUCCCCCCUCCCUUCCCACCUCCCCAUCCAACCCCCCAGCUACUCUCUGCGGCCGGUUGGUCCUGAACUGGUGGGUGCAGUUCCGAUGUUUAACCAAAUUCUCAAGCAAUUUCAAGGUAUUUGGAUUUUUUGAACCUGGGCCCUAACCGAAACGCGGAACGGCUUGCUUAUUAGACACCUCGAACGACAGGGCAGGGAGGAAACGGGAUACUCGCUGCCCUUCCCAGUCGCGCGUGAGUCAAAAGGUCCUGGCAGGAGAUGAUGUGAGGAGCGGCUGAAGUGGCAGGGAGGAAGGGAUGAGGGGCUUGGAGCGGAGGUCCACCACGCAAGGACUCGGGAAGCGGGCAAGUGGGCAAAACUCUGCUUCCGGGCUCUCGAUUUCUCGUUGAUCACUAAGUGGUAUUUUUCCCCCUUCUCUCGAUGGCAAAUGGGCGAAAUCAAGAUGACUUAACUUGGUAAAUUUAGAGAGAACGGCUCGGAGCAAGUGAGGUCUAACGGGCAGCUAAAAUUAUCUCCAAAUAAGAGAUUUUGACCCCCUCCCCCUAUCCUCUCCUCGAAUGUAUCCACCGGUGGGGAAGUGAGCGUCAUUACUUUCGGGGCGCCACGAACAGAUCUUACAGGUGAACAAGGUGAUGUCCAUCUUGUUUUAUGUGAUAUUUCUCGCUUAUCUCCGUGGCAUCCAAGGUAACAACAUGGAUCAAAGGAGUUUGCCAGAAGACUCGCUCAAUUCCCUCAUUAUUAAGCUGAUCCAGGCAGAUAUUUUGAAAAACAAGCUCUCCAAGCAGAUGGUGGACGUUAAGGAAAAUUACCAGAGCACCCUGCCCAAAGCUGAGGCUCCCCGAGAGCCGGAGCGGGGAGGGCCCGCCAAGUCAGCAUUCCAGCCGGUGAUUGCAAUGGACACCGAACUGCUGCGACAACAGAGACGCUACAACUCACCGCGGGUCCUGCUGAGCGACAGCACCCCCUUGGAGCCCCCGCCCUUGUAUCUCAUGGAGGAUUACGUGGGCAGCCCCGUGGUGGCGAACAGAACAUCACGGCGGAAACGGUACGCGGAGCAUAAGAGUCACCGAGGGGAGUACUCGGUAUGUGACAGUGAGAGUCUGUGGGUGACCGACAAGUCAUCGGCCAUCGACAUUCGGGGACACCAGGUCACGGUGCUGGGGGAGAUCAAAACGGGCAACUCUCCCGUCAAACAAUAUUUUUAUGAAACGCGAUGUAAGGAAGCCAGGCCGGUCAAAAACGGUUGCAGGGGUAUUGAUGAUAAACACUGGAACUCUCAGUGCAAAACAUCCCAAACCUACGUCCGAGCACUGACUUCAGAGAACAAUAAACUCGUGGGCUGGCGGUGGAUACGGAUAGACACGUCCUGUGUGUGUGCCUUGUCGAGAAAAAUCGGAAGAACAUGAAUUGGCAUCUCUCCCCAUAUAUAAAUUAUUACUUUAAAUUAUAUGAUAUGCAUGUAGCAUAUAAAUGUUUAUAUUGUUUUUAUAUAUUAUAAGUUGACCUUUAUUUAUUAAACUUCAGCAACCCUACAGUAUAUAAGCUUUUUUCUCAAUAAAAUCAGUGUGCUUGCCUUCCCUCAGGCCUCUCCCAUCUGUUAAAACUUGUUUUGUGAUCCGGCUCUCAGGAGUCACUCUGUAAAAUCUGUGUACACCAGUAUUUUGCAUUCAGUAUUGUCAAGGCCAUGACUGUUGUUUUAGUAAACUUGUUAAAAUCA